GGGAGCUCCGUUGUGCGUCGCUUAAGUGAGGGCGGCGGAUGGGCGAAGGUCCGGUGACUGCGACUGUCGCUGCUUUCUGAGGCCACAGGAAAGGGGCCGUCGGUCGCCGCCAUGACAGCGAGCGAGGCGGAGUUUCUUCCAUCUGCACCCAGUUGUCUUCAGCAUGGGGGAGCAGAACCACUCUCCCGGGAAGGAGCUUCAGCACAGGACGCGAGCAGAGGCUCCAGGAAAGAAAAGCUGGCAUUCCCAGGCCUAUGCCCUUGGGGCCGUUUCCAACUUUAUGUCUACUUUUCUGACCUUUCCUAUCUAUAAGGUUGUGUUCCGGCAACAGAUCCAUGCCAUGGCAGUGUCAGAGGCUGUGAGACAGCUUUGGCAUGAAGGUCCUCAAUACUUCUACCGGGGAAUCUACCCUCCUCUUCUCUCCAAGACGUUGCAAGGGACUCUUCUGUUUGGGACUUAUGAUAGCCUGCUGUGCUUUCUCUCUCCUGUUGGGCCACACACCCUGGGACACCGCUGGGCUGCCGGGCUCAUGUCUGGCGUGGUGGAGGCCGUGGCACUCAGCCCCUUUGAAAGGGUGCAAAAUGUGCUCCAGGAUGGUCGCAAGCAAGCUCGCUUCCCCAGCACCUUCAGCAUUCUCAAGGAAUUCAAUUCUUAUGGGCUUUGGGGGCGGCUGUCACUGGGCUACUAUCGUGGUUUCUGGCCUGUCCUGGCCAGGAACAGCCUGGGGAGUGCUCUAUAUUUUUCUUUCAAGGACCCCAUCCAGGAUGGCCUGGCAGAGCAAGGCCUGCCCCACUGGGUUCCUGCCUUGGUGUCUGGUAGUGUCAAUGGAACAAUCACCUGCCUAGUUCUGUAUCCUCUGAUUGUGCUGGUUGCUAAUAUGCAGUCCCAUAUUGGAUGGCAGAACAUGCCAAGCCUGUGGGCCUCUGCCCAGGAUGUAUGGAACACUCGGGGCCGAAAGCUGCUCCUGAUCUACCGUGGAGGCUCCCUAGUCAUCCUAAGGUCCAGUGUGACAUGGGGCCUCACUACGGCAAUCCAUGACUUCCUGCAGAGGAAGUCGCACUCCAGGAAAGAGCUGAAGACUGACUAGCUGCAGAAAGUGUGGCAUGGCAGCUUUGUUAUUCUAAAUCUUCCCUGGUUGGUUCUAUAUAGCUUACUUCUUUGGCUAGGUUGCCUAAUACAGCCAUCCUUUAGCAUCUAUAAACUCAUUGCAUGGGAGAAGUUCCCAACUACCAACCUGUUGAGCAAGGACAAAGCCCAAAAGUAUUCCUUAGUCAAAAAGAAACGUUCACCCCAGUCUCUCCACAGUUUCAGUAGCCUCAGAGCCAGGAGGCCUUUAAAUAACAUGUAACCCAGAUUAAGUGUCAUUCCUUUAAGGAAUUCCUUGGCAAUAAACAGAAACUUAAAAAGAUGACCUUACUUAGGCACUCUGAGCUCUGGGACCCCUCUAGGUGUCCUCCAGACCAAACUGAGUGGAACUCCAAUUUCAAAGAACUAUGCUUGACUCUUAGGAUGGGAAUUCCAUAAAACUUCUCAGAUGGCUACAUUUUCAUGAUAUUGUUCACUGCCUCUACCACCACCUCUCACUUCUCAAGGCUGUGGGUCCUACUUUCAGGGUAGCAGCUGUGGCUGGAAAUCCUAAAUUAGGCUUGCAUGAACUCGUCAGGUGCCACAAGAACUAGUGGGGCUGGAGAUGGGAGUGAGAAGAGGCGUGGCCCAUGGAUGGAAAGAAUAAAAACUUUGAAAGAAAAGAUUUAAUUACAUGCAAAAUAGAAACAUUUGCUAUAGUCUGCUUGGUGUUAUCUGCUAGGACAUUUCUGAGAGCAAGGUGAUAACAUUGCCUAGAAACCGUUUGAGUUUCCCUAAGAAACCUGGAAGUGAAGUGACCAUAUCUCUUCACAGAAAAUUGCAUAUUUUGUUGAUGUGGUUAAAUGUAGUUACUAUGACAUAAAGAUCAGAAAUCUUAGCCUGUCAUUCAGAGCCAUUCAAAAUAUGGUCAUCAUAUAACUUUCAACAUAUUGUCACUCCACUUACAUAAACCCCAAACACUAGCCAUAAUGAACUAUUGUUCUCUCCCCAGACAUUCCAUGAACUUUCCCAUGGCCAUACUCUGGCCCACACUAUUCUUUCCACCUGCAGUGCUCCUUCUUCACAUGCCAGUCUACCAAAAUCCUUCCAGUUCCUUGAAGCCCAGCUCAGAGGUCACCUUCUCUAUGGAGUUCUUGAUUUUCCCCAACUGAAUGUGACAUUAGUCUCUGUGAUGCCCCUUUCUUUUUUUUUUUUUUGAGACGGAGUUUCGCUCUUGUUGCCCAGGCUGGAGUGCCAAUGGUGUGAUCUCAGCUCACUGCAACCUCCACCUCCCGGAUUCAAGUGAUUCUCCUGCCUCAGCCUCCCGAGUAGCUGGAAUUACAGGCGCCCACCACCAUGCCUGGCUAAUUUUGUAUUUUUAGUAGAGAUGGGGUCUCUCCAUGUUGGUCAGGCUGGUCUCGAACUCCCAACCUCAUCAGGUGAUCCACCCACCUCGGUCUCCCAAAGUGCUGGGAUUACAGGCGUGAGCCACCGCGCCCAGCCUCUGUGAUGCCCCUUUCUAACAGCACUUCAUACAGGGUACUGAUUCCAUUAUGUCACUAAUCUCAUGUGACCCUUUGUUCUUGUAUUCUUCAAUACCUCCUACUAGACUGUAAAACUCAUUGAAAGCAGGGAUUUUUGUAUGCAUUUUAAAAUCUUCCAUUGUGCCUAGGUGCUCAAUAACGUUGGUCAAAUUACUGAGUUGAUUAUCAAGCUGUGAUAUGGUAUAUCCUCAGGGUGCUGUCCCUUGUACAUGACGAUAAAGUUAUUGACUCACUGUCAGCAAGACACGUGCCUUUGGGCUGUGUUUUUGCUUUCUUUUAAUAAUUGAUUUAGUUUUGUGCUAAUGAUAAUGAUGCUGCUACUGAUAAUAAUAAUAACAAUAAUAAAAAUUACUUUCAACUGGCACAUUUGAUGAGUUUAUAUUACUGAUGGCAUGUUUGCUAUUAGCACCAGUUCAGGAACUGAAAUUUCACAAACAGAAUCACACUGUACAACUGUACCAUUUGUUUCAACUCUGGAAUUUUGAGGAUUUCCAAGAUGACAUGUGUUAUAGUUUCCCCCUACAGAUAUCUUAGUAAUGCCCUCCUCUUGCAUCUCCUUACUGAACCAAAUUUGUCCUGUAUUUGUCUUACUUGGUUGUAGAUUUAGCAGUGAGAACUUCUCACUGAAUGCCACAGAAAUUAAAGACAUGGUUGUUGGAGGUAUGAUGUCAGAGAGCAUUUGCCACCAAGGUUGGCAGAAAAUGGCUGGUCCAGGAGAGCUGAAGAUGAGCUUCCACAUCUGCAGAUCGGGAUGUGUUGGGACAGUACUCAACUUGUGGAUUCAAGGAAGUAUGAACACAGAGUCUGCAUAAGGAAAGGAAAAAGAUGCAUUCAUCUCCCAAGUACACUGGUGAUUUCCACUUAUGUCAUUCUGUCCAUCCAUGUCCCUUUCUUCAUUUUAACUUCUUAUUUAAAAAUAAUUUCAAACAUUUAAAAAUGUUGCAAGCAUAAAUAAAGCUUAAAGAACACCCAUGUCCCCUUUACCCUAAUUCCCCUAUUAUUAAUGUUUCUCCCCAUUUGCUUUAUUAUUUAAGUGUGCACUCUGUCUAUACACACACAGGAUAUUUUUUCCCUGAACUAUCUGAGAGUUGCAUACAUCAGUUUUCAAUAUUCCUAGAUUCAAUGUUUGUAGAUCCAAAUUAUUUUUUAAGAGACCGUGUUUUAUCUCUGACAAUGGGACAGUUAUUACAGAAUAUAAUAAAAUGAAAACUCACACAAUAUAUGUGAUAUUGUGAAAUAUAUACUUGGUCUUUGAUCCUGUUUCUUGGCAUACAACUCCUAAAAUCCUUAGAAUUUCCAAAGUGAUAUCUUUUUGUAUGCUAAUAAUUGACUGAUGGCUGGCAGCCUCUGGUUGCUUCAGGAUGGGAACUAGUCACCAGGAAGACCAAGGCACCAUUAGAGGGUUGGGACUUAACAGCCUCAUUCCCGACCUCCAGGGAGGGGAGAGGGAUGGAAGGUUAAGUUGAUCACCAGUGGCCAAUGAUUUAAUCAAUCAUGCCUACGCAAUGAAGCUUCCAUAAAAACCCCAAAGCACUGGGUUUGGAGAGCUUCCAGAUAGCUGAACAUGUGGAGGUUCCUGGAGGGUGGUGACCCAGGGAGGGCACAGAAGCUCUGAGCCCCUUCCGCAGUACCUCACCCUAUGCAUCUCUUCAUCUCUAUCCUUUGAUAUAUCCUUUAUAAUAAAGUGGUAAACGUUAAGUAUUUCCCCAAGUUCUGUGACCCUUUCUGGCAAAUUAAACCCAAAGAAGGGGUCAUGUGAACUCAAACUUGAAGCCCAUCUGUCAGAAGUUCUGGAGGCUUGGAUUUGCGACUGGUGUCUGAAGGGCCUGGGAACAGUCUUGUGAAACCUAGUCCUCAGCUUGUGGGAUAUGACGCUAUCUCCAGGUAGAUUGUGUCAGAAUGGAAUUGGAGUACACCCAGCUGGUGUUCGCUGCAGAACUGAUUGCUCACUUAGUGUGUGGGAAAACUCCACACAUCUGGACAUGGAAAUAUUCUGUGCUGAUUGCCGUGGUGUAAGAGCAAUGCAAAAAGUUUGGGUAUUUUCCCCUCGGAGUAUAUUUUAAAGCUAAAUUGCUAAUAAUUGCUUAAAUUUACUAUAUUUGCCUUUAUAAAAACUUUAUGUAUGUUGAAGCUUGAAGCUAUGCAAUUAUAAUAUAAACAUGGAUUUACAACUAAAGCAUGUUAUAAUUUAAAUAAUUGAGUUUUUCAAAUCGGUUCAUAUGAAAUCCUAGGCAAUAUUGUAAAAUUAUACAGACCUGUCAACUUUUUCCACUUAAAAGUUGUGAGCAAAAUUUAAGGGCAUAGUCGUUUUCAAGUAAUUUUAAAUGUCAAUGUUAAUAUUUAGUUUAGUGAUGUUAAUGGAGCUAUGUUUUCUGAUAUUAAAAAUGAGUUUUAGGAGUUGAGACCAAUAAAAUAAGGAGGUAAUAAAUAUCUAUAUCUGUUUAAACACAUAAAAUAUACAAUUUAACACUAAAAUUACUUGGUAUAAAAAGUCAAAAAAAAGAAUAAAAAGCCAUCAUACAACACAAUAUAUGCGUGAUAUAUAUUUUUCUCUAAAUAUAAACUACAUCAGCUUUUAUAAAGCUCAAGUUGAAAUAAUAACGUUUUAUGACAAAUCAUUAUAUGGUAUAUUCUGACUUAAUUUUGCAUUUACAAUUUAUUUUUAAACACUAAAUAGCAUUAUAAUUUUACUGGGAUAACUAUAUAUAGUGUAGUAUAUUAAAGUUAAUAAAAUGACGUUGCAUAUGAGAGAAAAAGCAUAAUAAAUCAGAAACAAUAUAAAAAGCUUUCAGAAAAGAUAAAAAUAUUGUAUUUCUCUAGUCUGUUCACUCUCCAGUGUCUCUGGUUCUUUCAUAUCAUCUUCCUUUCCUCAAAUCUUUUAAUACUCCCUCCCUCAUCAUUUCCAACUAGUGACCCUACUUUCUAUUUCAUUAAGAAAACAGAUACAUUCAGAAGAGAACUGCCAGUUUAAAGAACAUUUACAAAGCCAUCACCCAUGUAAUAACCAGCCAGAGCAAGAAAUAGAGCCCUUUAAUAACCUACUCUUCUCCCCCCACCACUGAUGACACCGCUCCCUCCAUCUUAGGUGUAGCCCCCAUGCUGACUUUUGUAAUAAUAAUUUCUUUGCUUUUGUUUAUAAGUUUUCUUCCUUAUAAGCAUCUCUAAACAACAGUUUUGUUUUACAGAUGUUCAAACAUUAAAUGCUUUUUAGACUUGGAAUUGUGACUAUCUUGUUUCACUCCACAUUGCUUGUGAGACUCAUUGAUAUUGCAGAUAGCUGUAGUUGAUCCAUUUUUAUUGUUGUACAGUUUACCAUUGUAUAAAUAUACCAUGAUUUAUUCAUGAUAACUUUGAGGAACAUUCUGGUUGUUUGCAGGUUUUAUUUUUACAGUUCAUUAGUUUUAUUGAUGUAUAAUAAUUGUAUAUGUUUAUGGGGUAUAUGUGAUAUUUUGAUACAUGUGUACAAUGUGUAAUGAUUAAAUCAAGGUAAUUGGGAUAUCCAUCAGCUCAAACAUUUAUCAUUUCUUUGCAUUGGGAACAUUCCAAAUCUUCUCUUCUAGCUAUUUUGAAAUACACAAUAAAUUGAAUACUGUGGUCA